GGGUCUUUUGCGGCUGCAGCGGGCUUGUAGGUUCGUGGACGCGGCAUUGGGGGAGGGGACGGGGGUCGCGGGGCUAUUGGGGGUCCCAGUCCGGCUUAAGACCUCUGGGCGUGGUGGGCACCGGCCUUCGCCGUCGGAGCAGGGGUCCCAGACUCGCACCCAAAAGUUCCCGUCGGGCCCGAGCGGGGAGGAGCUGCGGGGCGGGCAGAGGCGGAGAUGGCGGAGGGCGGUGGGACGUGAUGCGCGGGUCAGAGCCGGGCCUUGAGAAGGAACUGGAGGCCCCUGGCAGCGGUGUCCCCUCGAGGACCCCUCUGCCGGGCUCACCAGGUGGCUGGCGGAGAGCCGGAGAGUUGGGCGGGAGGGAAGCAGGGUUUGGCGACCAGGUUUAGCAGGCCUUGGAAUCCUGGAGCCCAGCCCCCAACCCCAUUCCCACUUGGCCGGAUGGUUAAGGGCCUAGCGUGCUGGCUGCGGUGUGGCCACCUUCCCCUUCUCCGACUCCGUAUCUCUUUUUCCAGGUGUCCGGCUUUGCUGGCCCAGCAAGCCUGAUAAGCAUGAAGCUCUUAUCUUUGGUGGCUGUGGUCGGGUGUUUGCUGGUGCCCCCAGCUGAAGCCAACAAGAGUUCUGAAGAUAUCCGGUGCAAAUGCAUCUGUCCACCUUAUAGAAACAUCAGUGGGCACAUUUACAACCAGAAUGUAUCCCAGAAGGACUGCAACUGCCUGCACGUGGUGGAGCCCAUGCCAGUGCCUGGCCAUGACGUGGAGGCCUACUGCCUGCUGUGCGAGUGCAGGUACGAGGAGCGCAGCACCACCACCAUCAAGGUCAUCAUUGUCAUCUACCUGUCCGUGGUGGGUGCCCUGUUGCUCUACAUGGCCUUCCUGAUGCUGGUGGACCCUCUGAUCCGAAAGCCGGAUGCAUAUACUGAGCAACUGCACAAUGAGGAGGAGAAUGAGGAUGCUCGCUCUAUGGCAGCAGCUGCUGCAUCCCUCGGGGGACCCCGAGCAAACACAGUCCUGGAGCGUGUGGAAGGUGCCCAGCAGCGGUGGAAGCUGCAGGUGCAGGAGCAGCGGAAGACAGUCUUCGAUCGGCACAAGAUGCUCAGCUAGAUGGGCUGGUGUGGUUGGGUCAAGGCCCCAACACCAUGGCUGCCAGCUUCCAGGCUGGACAAAGCAGGGGGCUACUUCUCCCUUCCCUCGGUUCCAGUCUUCCCUUUAAAAGCCUGUGGCAUUUUUCCUCCUUCUCCCUAACUUUAGAAAUGUUGUACUUGGCUAUUUUGAUUAGGGAAGAGGGAUGUGGUCUCUGAUCUCUGUUGUCUUCUUGGGUCUUUGGGGUUGAAGGGAGGGGGAAGGCAGGCCAGAAGGGAAUGGAGACAUUCGAGGCGGCCUCAGGAGUGGAUGCGAUCUGUCUCUCCUGGCUCCACUCUUGCCGCCUUCCAGCUCUGAGUCUUGGGAAUGUUGUUACCCUUGGAAGAUAAAGCUGGGUCUUCAGGAACUCAGUGUCUGGGAGGAAAGCAUGGCCCAGCAUUCAGCAUGUGUUCCUUUCUGCAGUGGUUCUUAUCACCACCUCCCUCCCAGCCCCAGCGCCUCAGCCCCAGCCCCAGCUCCAGCCCUGAGGACAGCUCUGAUGGGAGAGCUGGGCCCCCUGAGCCCACUGGGUCUUCAGGGUGCACUGGAAGCUGGUGUUCGCUGUCCCCUGUGCACUUCUCGCACUGGGGCAUGGAGUGCCCAUGCAUACUCUGCUGCCGGUCCCCUCACCUGCACUUGAGGGGUCUGGGCAGUCCCUCCUCUCCCCAGUGUCCACAGUCACUGAGCCAGACGGUCGGUUGGAACAUGAGACUCGAGGCUGAGCGUGGAUCUGAACACCACAGCCCCUGUACUUGGGUUGCCUCUUGUCCCUGAACUUCGUUGUACCAGUGCAUGGAGAGAAAAUUUUGUCCUCUUGUCUUAGAGUUGUGUGUAAAUCAAGGAAGCCAUCAUUAAAUUGUUUUAUUUCUCUCA